CUCCCUCCCUCGGUCCCCGGGGCCGGCGGACCCGCGGGCAGGCACUGCCCGGGCUGGACGACGUCUGGCCGGCUCCCGGCGAAGGGCAGCGGAGGAGCGGCCCAGAGCGCGCAGCUAGGGCACUGGCGAAACCCCGGGACAGUCCCUCUCCGUGCGGGGGCGGCGCAGAGCAGUCCCAUCCCCGGGGUCCCGGGCGCGGCUGACUGCCGGCUGGUUCCCUGCGCGCAGUAGCUCCCCGAGCCGGGCUGCACCGGAGGCGGCGAGAUGGUCGCGCGCGUCGGCCUCCUGCUGCGCGCCCUGCAGCUGCUACUGUGGGGCCACCUGGACGCCCAGCCCGCGGAGCGCGGAGGCCAGGAGCUGCGCAAGGAGGCGGAGGCAUUCCUAGAGAAGUACGGAUACCUCAAUGAACAGGUCCCCAAAGCUCCCACCUCCACUCGAUUCAGCGAUGCCAUCAGAGCGUUUCAGUGGGUGUCCCAGCUACCUGUCAGCGGCGUGUUGGACCGCGCCACCCUGCGCCAGAUGACUCGUCCCCGCUGCGGGGUUACAGAUACCAACAGUUAUGCGGCCUGGGCUGAGAGGAUCAGUGACUUGUUUGCUAGACACCGGACCAAAAUGAGGCGUAAGAAACGCUUUGCAAAGCAAGGUAACAAAUGGUACAAGCAGCACCUCUCCUACCGCCUGGUGAACUGGCCUGAGCAUCUGCCGGAGCCGGCAGUUCGGGGCGCCGUGCGCGCCGCCUUCCAGUUGUGGAGCAACGUCUCAGCGCUGGAGUUCUGGGAGGCCCCAGCCACAGGCCCCGCUGACAUCCGGCUCACCUUCUUCCAAGGGGACCACAACGAUGGGCUGGGCAAUGCCUUUGAUGGCCCAGGGGGCGCCCUGGCGCACGCCUUCCUGCCCCGCCGCGGCGAAGCGCACUUCGACCAAGAUGAGCGCUGGUCCCUGAGCCGCCGCCGCGGGCGCAACCUGUUCGUGGUGCUGGCGCACGAGAUCGGUCACACGCUUGGCCUCACCCACUCGCCCGCGCCGCGCGCGCUCAUGGCGCCCUACUACAAGAGGCUGGGCCGCGACGCGCUGCUCAGCUGGGACGACGUGCUGGCCGUGCAGAGCCUGUAUGGGAAGCCCCUAGGGGGCUCAGUGGCCGUCCAGCUCCCAGGAAAGCUGUUCACUGACUUUGAGACCUGGGACUCCUACAGCCCCCAAGGAAGGCGCCCUGAAACGCAGGGCCCUAAAUACUGCCACUCUUCCUUCGAUGCCAUCACUGUAGACAGGCAACAGCAACUGUACAUUUUUAAAGGGAGCCAUUUCUGGGAGGUGGCAGCUGAUGGCAACGUCUCAGAGCCCCGUCCACUGCAGGAAAGAUGGGUCGGGCUGCCCCCCAACAUUGAGGCUGCGGCAGUGUCAUUGAAUGAUGGAGAUUUCUACUUCUUCAAAGUGCAAUCCGUUUGAUUGAUAUGAAUACCAACCAUCGUGGGCUCCAGCUUAAAGGAGAGCAGAGGGGGUCGAUGCUGGAGGUUCCGGGGCCCCAAGCCAGUGUGGGGUCUCCCACAGCUGUGCCGGGCAGGGGGCCUGCCCCGCCAUCCUGACGCCGCCCUCUUCUUCCCUCCUCUGCGCCGCCUCAUCCUCUUCAAGGGUGCCCGCUACUACGUGCUGGCCCGAGGGGGACUGCAAGUGGAGCCCUACUACCCCCGAAGUCUGCAGGACUGGGGAGGCAUCCCUGAGGAGGUCAGCGGCGCCCUGCCGAGGCCCGAUGGCUCCAUCAUCUUCUUCCGAGAUGACCGCUACUGGCGCCUCGACCAGGCCAAACUGCAGGCAACCACCUCGGGCCGCUGGGCCACCGAGCUGCCCUGGAUGGGCUGCUGGCAUGCCAACUCGGGGAGCGCCCUGUUCUGAAGGCACCUCCUCACCUCAGAAACUGGUGGUGCUCUCAGGGCAAAAUCAUGUUCCCCACCCCCGGGGCAGAACCCCUCUUAGAAGCCUCUGAGUCCCUCUGCAGAAGACCGGGCAGCAAAGCCUCCAUCUGGAAGUCUGUCUGCCUUUGUUCCUUGAAGAAUGCAGCAUUGUCUUUGUCUGUCCCCACCACAUGGAGGUGGGGGUGGGAUCAAUCUUAGGAAAAGCAAAAAAGGGUCCCAGAUCCCUUGGCCCUUUCCUCCGAGGACUUCUAUCCUCCCCAGGCCUUUGUUUCUUCGGCUAAAGGUACAGUUCCUUUCAAGAGGUAACAGCACUGGGAUCCAAGCAGGGGGAUGAAAAACUCAGCAGAGAAAUUCGAGACCAUUUUGCAAGACUGUGCCCUUCUCCUCAGGACCCCCUGGCUCAGUUCUUGAAAAACGGUGUCAUAUUUAGUCAGAGGCCCCACCCCCAGGAAGCAUGGAUGGGGAUGAAGGCACAGGCGUCUCCAACCUCAGAGGCCCUUUGUGGGGUCAGGACACAGAGUGGGAGGGAGACUGAUGCAGGCCUACCAGUCCCUGGCUUUUUGUCUGGGGCUGGAAUAAAGAGGUGCCUUCAGCUGGUGGGCCGAGAGGCAGGAA